AGCUUCCAGUCGCUCGAGAGCGGAGAGCGGCACCAUGGCCCCGCGGGGGCGGCGGCGGCCGCGGCCUCACAGGUCUGAGGGGUAAGUACUGCCGACCCUCGGGAGCGCGGGGCCGGAGACCAGCUUGAACUGCUUCCUCGCCUGCCGUGGUUUGCGCCUCCCGGCGCUGUUGGUGCUCCACUGUGGAGGUCGCCCGAGUGGCCAAUCGCCCGGGUCCCCGGCUUCCUCCUCAGUCUAGUGGGGAUAACAGUGAUCCCACCUGCACGGGCCUGUCGGGGCCUAACACUGCCUGGCGGGUGGGAGAGACGUCAGCCAGUGUCGUGUCGUUUUGUGGGGAGGGGGAGUGCCGUCCAAAGUAGUGAGUCUCAAAGUGCUAGCUUGAAAGCAAAAUAUUCAGCAAAUACGUAUUGCCUGCGGUUUGCCAGACUUUGUUAGUGGAGUUUUAUUCUCUGACUGGGAAUCAGUUUUCUUAUUUUGAAGACCCUGGUGUUUUCUUACUGCAAACCACAGACCGUAAACUGGAGCAUAAAUCCGGCUGGGGGACCGAGCUGCCGCUUGCGGUUCUCCAGGAUGGCUCGAGCGGUUUUUGUUUACCAAAGAAAGCGAGCGUUUGGUCGGUUGCAAAACGCGCUCUAGAAUGCUGGUCGCUGAUUCGUUGGCGAAUGGCCAUCCAAGGCCCGGCCUGGAUCUGGCGGGAAGGGUCUCGGCUUGCUGCAGACGGUGCACAAAGCCAUACGCCAAGACGAUCUGAAGAGAACAGGAGUUCCCCCGGGCCUGGGAAGGCUGCCUGGAGGAGGAGCGCAAGACGUUCAAAGAACACUUUAGAAAGAACACAUUCCAUGAAAGAUAAAGCUGGUCAAAAGUGCAAGCCUAUUGACGUGUUCGACUUUCCUGAUAAUUCUGAUGUCUCAAGCAUUGGCAGGCUGGGUGAAAAUGAGAAAGAUGAAGAAACUUAUGAGACCUUUGAUCCUCCUUUACAUAGCACAGCUAUAUAUGCUGAUGAAGAAGAAUUCUCCAAACAUUGUGGACUGUCUCUCUCUUCAACUCCUCCAGGAAAAGAAGCAAAAAGAAGUUCAGACACUUCUGGAAAUGAAGCAAGUGAAAUCGAAUCUGUAAAAAUUAGUGCAAAAAAGCCAGGAAGAAAGCUCAGGCCCAUUAGUGAUGACUCUGAAAGCAUUGAAGAAAGUGAUACAAGGAGAAAAGUUAAAUCAGCAGAGAAAAUAAGUACACAACGUCAUGAGGUUAUUCGAACCACAGCGUCUUCAGAACUUUCAGAGAAACCAGCUGAGUCUGUCACUUCUAAAAAGACAGGACCCCUUAGUGCCCAGCCCUCUGUUGAAAAAGAGAACUUGGCAAUAGAAAGUCAAUCGAAAACUCAGAAAAAAGGGAAGAUAUCUCAUGACAAAAGGAAGAAAUCAAGAAGUAAAGCCAUAGGCUCAGAUACUUCUGACAUUGUGCACAUUUGGUGUCCAGAAGGAAUGAAAACCAGUGACAUCAAGGAGUUGAAUAUUGUUUUGCCUGAAUUUGAGAAAACCCACCUAGAGCAUCAACAAAGAAUAGAAUCUAAAGUUUGUAAGGCAGCCAUCGCCACAUUUUAUGUUAAUGUUAAAGAACAAUUCAUCAAAAUGCUUAAAGAAAGCCAGAUGUUGACAAAUCUGAAAAGGAAGAAUGCUAAGAUGAUUUCAGAUAUCGAAAAGAAAAGGCAGCGUAUGAUUGAAGUCCAGGAUGAACUGCUUCGGUUAGAGCCACAGCUGAAACAACUACAAACAAAAUAUGAUGAACUUAAAGAGAGAAAGUCUUCCCUUAGGAAUGCAGCAUAUUUCUUAUCUAAUUUAAAACAGCUUUAUCAAGAUUAUUCAGAUGUUCAAGCUCAAGAACCAAACGUAAAGGAAACGUAUGAUUCAUCCAGCCUUCCAGCUCUGUUAUUUAAAGCAAGAACACUUCUGGGAGCCGAAAGCCAUCUGCGAAAUAUCAACCAUCAGUUAGAGAAGCUCCUUGACCAGGGAUGAGAAGAGCAGUCUACUAAAAUGUGCCUAUAGGAAGACUAGUCUCAUGCUGUUACCUUCUGAAACUGUACCUUUAUAAAUCAAUUGUUUUGCAAAGAAGUUAUGGCCUACUUAGAAUCUAAAAUUUGUUAUUCAAAUUAAAUGGCUGUGAACAAUGUUAAAUAGCAUCAGUUUGUCCAAUAGUUUUAAAGGCCAUAAUCAUCUUUUCUGGUUAAUAUCUUGAGUAAUUUUAAAAUGUUGACACCUUAAUCGGUCCCAGGUAUGAGCUAUAAUAAACUUGUAAAAUUAAGUUGAUGUGAACAUAAUUUUGAUUAAUUAAUAAGGCGAUUUCUCCUGAAUUUACACCAAAGCUAAUUUUUAAUGAAAUUGGUUUACAGAAGUAAAAAACAAAAAUUGGAAAGCAAAGUAAUAAAACUUAGUUUAUAUAAACAGGUUGAAUGAUAUAUUUAUCAAAUCUCACAGACAUCAGGCAAAUUAUAGCCUGGUGACAAAAGUGUUCAUAGUGAAUUAGUUACUCUUGUAAUACUUCUAUAAUUAGUUCAUCAGGAAUUUCAUCCACUUCACUGUUAUAACUGAGAAGACUGUUCUCUGCAGCUUCAGCUAAUUCAGCAUCUUCAGUAGCUUCUAAAAAAUAAGCAUCAUCAAUGCCAUUAUCCCAGACAGCAUCAGCAGAUGCACCUGUUGACAGCCUGCUAGGUGAUGGUUUAUGAGGAUUCUGGGUUUCAUUGCUCCUAGUUUCAUCUGCUUCAUCUGUUGUAAACUCUUCUUCCUUUAUUUCAGUGGUGAAGGGAUAGAGAGUGGGAUAGGAAAAUAUUUACUCAGGAUAUGUGAUUUAACCUUAUACUCUAUGUUGAAGUAAGGUAUUAAGUGACAGAUACUAAAGUGAAUAUGCAGGAGGAAUGCUGUCUCCGAUAUCUCACCGUGGGAAUGAGUGCACUGAUUCAAACGUUGCUGCACUGAAGCUCAGACACACUUGAAACUCCAAAUUUGAAAUUACCUACAGUUCUGUGCACAUACUUUUCAAUACUCCCCGACGGAAGAGCAAGGGUGGAUUUAAUUUUUUAACAAGUGGACAGUCCAGCUGAAGACAAAUCAGAAGAUAAAUUUGCUAUCUUGACAAUGGACUUAGUACCCAUGCUUUAAAUUUUAAAGUAUUUAGCAAAUCGUAAACAUGGAUUGAAAAAAGAUUAAAAACAGUUGCCAAAA